AAUUCUGACUAGCCUGCCGGCUGCUCACCUCCUGCUGUGUGGCCCAGUUCCUAACAGGCCACGAACUGGUACUGAUUGUUCCCCAGAGUUUGGGGACCCCUUGUCUUGACAGUAUCAUGCACAGAUACCUCCCCAACCCCCUCUCCACCAAACUCCUGGUAACCACCAUUUUAUUCUCUACUUCUACAGCGUCUUGCCCUGUCGCCACGCUGGAGUCCACUGCAACCUCCGCAUCCUGGGUUCAAGCAAUUCUCCUGCCUCAGCCUCCCAAGUAGCUGGGACUACGGGUGCGUGCCACCACACCCAGCUAAUUUUUGUAUCUUUAGUAGAGAUGGGGUUCACCAUGUUGGCCAGGGUGGUCUCAAUCUGUUGACCUCUUGAUCUGCCCUCCUCGGCCUCCCAAAAUGCUGGGAUUACAGGCAUGAGCCACCGCGCCCAGCCAGUACAUAGAUUUUCUAAAGUGUUCAACACUCUUAUCAAUUCAGAUUCCACCAUAAUUUAUAUGAUCAAUCAAGCACUGCUUUGUUUCUCUGUAGGUCUCCUGGAAUACAACAUAGUCAGAGAUGUGUAGAGUAUGGUCCUUCUGGGUUUGCCAAAUUUUGUGCUGAAGGAAAAUGAUGGCUCCACCGCUCUUCCUGCCUAACUCGUAGAAAGGCAGCAUGGUAUUGUGAUAGAAACAUGAGCUUUGAAGAUAAGCAGUCAGAUUCUGAUUCCUGUUCUUCUAAUAGUCCAGCCUUGUAAAGAUCACUUAUCCUCAUAGUUAGCAAGACUUCCUCAUUUAAAAAAUUCUUUCCUCAUAGGGUUGUUGUGAAGACUAAGUGAAUUAAGUUCUGUGAAAAAAUCUAGCACAGUGUUUAGCACAUGAAUAGUUUUCUCCAUAUAUGUGGCCUCUCUCCUGGGAUGAUCACCUUGUCCCAGUUUGUCCAGGGUUUCCCUAGUUUUAUCACAGAAAGUCUCAUGUGUACUAGGAAUCAAUCUCUCUCUUUCUCUCUCUUUUUUUUUUUUUUUUUUGAGAUGGAGUUUUUGCUCUGUUGUCCAGAUUGGAGAGCAGUGGUGCAAUCUCAGCGCACUGCAACCUCCGCCUCCUGGAUUCAAGCAAUUUUCCUGCCUCAGCCUCCCAAGUAGCUGGGAUUACAGAUGCCUGCCACCACACCCAGCUAAUUUUUGUAUUUUUAGUAGAGGCGAGGUUUCACCAUGUUGUCCAGACUGAUCUCGAACUCUUGACCUCAGGUGAUCCGUCUGCCUCUGCCUCCUGAAGUACUAGGAUUACAGGCGUGAGCCACCACGCCUGGCCUCUCUUCUCUCUCUCUCACUUGACUUUUCUAGGCUUAUUGGCCAUUCCUUGAAUAAGGUACAGUCAAGUUUUACUUUAGACUUUUAAGUAGCUCAGAAUAGAGUUCCUUAGCUUGUUGGUUUUUACUUAUUUUUUUCAUUAAUGUUUCAAGGUAUAUUAUGAGGUUGCAUUAUUUAAUUGCUUUGUUGAUUGAGCCAGGCAGAUCUUUCAUUUAUUAGCUGGCCUGAUAUCAGGGCAGGAAAGCUUAUGAGUUACUUUGUAAAGUGAUGGUUUUAUUAAAGGUGGUAAUUUUGAUCAGCUGACCUAUUGGUGGGUUCUGAUUACUUUACAGAAGUGGAUGGUAUUGACAAGCCUCCAUCUACUUGGAAGUUUUAAAAUGUGUUCUUUUUAUUAAAAGGACUUCAUCCUGUGAAACUAGUUUCUUCAAAUUGAAGUUCUCUCAGUCUAGGCAUGAUGAGUUACAAAAAUGAUUGUUUGUAGUAUUUUGGAAUUGGUUUCCACCUUUAUAUAAACUCAAAUGUCAAUUUAAUGUGUUCAGUAAGCCAAGCAACCUUUCUAAUGAAACAAGUAUAAUUAUGAUUUAUUUAUAUUUUUAUUUCAUUUCUCAUUUUUUUCAGCAAUCUUUCCUGUCCUCAACUAUGUUUCCUUUUUAAUUUAAAAAAAUCAAGUAGAAAACAAAUAUCUGGCUUUUUUGUCAAUGUCAUGGUCUUAUGUCAAGAUCUUGAAAGGUAUCUCUCCAAAUUAUUGUUCUGCUAUAGUUAUUUCUAUCAAAGAAGUCCUCUUGUAUAGCUAUUUGUUGAAUUGUGUACCUACUGAAUUAGUCAAAGCUCUAGCUAAAACCAUUUUUUUCUUUACCUCUCCCCUCCCCCAAAACUUGCUUUUGUUAUGUAUUGGCUUGCUAAUCCUUGUGUUGAGCAGUAUCAGACAUCACCUUUCUUGGGGGCAGUUAGUCCACUCUUCCGCUUUCUUUGUCAGAGGGCUCCCUUAAUAGGAGAAGUCAACAGGGAGGACAAAAAGGAUUGAAAGUUGUAUUUAAUCAGGGUCAGAGAGGUGGUGUUCAGAGUGACGGGCCCACAGGCAGGCUGGCCUUUUAUGCUUGCCGACGCAGAUGGUCCCAGAGCAUUCAGCUAAGUGAAGAGAAAGCUGCCCAGUGAAAGCUAUUGUAGGGUAGCAUCGUUACAGUUGAGAAAGGUUGCCAGGGGUAACUAGAGAGUAUCACCAGUAUCGUGUGAUCACUAGGCUGUGCCAUUGAAAAUGUUAGACUGAGGAUUGUAUUGGGUCCCUUGGCAUCUUGAUGUUCAUAUGUAAGCAGUAUUAGCUUACAUUAGUGUUUUUAAUUUAGUUUUUUCUGUUUUCUUCCCUUUGUUCUUUCCCUGCCUUUUUUAAUAUAUAAAACAUAGACUUAUUUUAAUUCACAAUUUUGUAAAACCUUCUGAAAACAUACCAUUAUUUAAUAAUAUAUCUCUUAUAGGCUUUAUGGUUUGGUAUAAACUAUACCAAAUUUUUGUGAAUAAAUUGGAUUUAUGAAAAUGAGGUGUAAUAUUUCUCGUUUAAACAGCUCUAAGUUGAUUUUCCAUUGCUCUGAAACUGCCCUAGUAUAUCCCAAGAUGGGUAGUUUGUUUUUCUUUGUGAUUUUAAGUAACUUAUUUUAAAAUAUGUUAGUAUUUACCUGAAAACAGUAGAUAGCAUUGAGUGCAGGGUUGUGACCAAGAACUCCCAAAUAUUUAUGAAAUCUAUCUUCAAUUUUUGCCUAAGGCAAAAGUAAAAAUAUGCAUCCCAAAUGAGCCAGAACCAAAAUAGUGUAACAAUCAUUGGUCUCAAUUUAAUAUACUUAAUAUACUUUGAAUAUGAUUUUAAUAUGCCAGUUUUGGAAUUCCUUAAUUUCAUCCCUUCUAUUGUCCCCCGGAUAUUUUAAGAAAUUACUUAUAGUCACAUACAAAAUGUAAACACAGUAGUCUCCUGCCGUCACUAGAGGAAAACACAUAGAGAUUUCUAUUCAAUGUAAAAGUGAAAUUUGAAGUGUAACUAACGUUCAAGGUGAAAUGAUAAUAACUUUGCAAAUUAUUGUUUUAACUUAGAUUACCAGUCAACCCAAUUUAAGUCACCCUUACGUCAGUCAGAGCUGAUUUUGACUUAAUACUGCUUUCUCACCUGUUGAGAGAACAUUAAGUGAGGACAAACAUAGUACCAUCCUGUAAUACCAACAUUGGUAUUUGAGAGCUAAUCAUCUCCAAUGUUAUUAUUUUGUGUUAGAGGUAACUUUUAGAAAUUGGUGAAUUUCAAGUGGAGCCAGGCUUUAAAAUGCCUUCUGAGACCCCCACUUAAUAGUUCUGACUCUAAAUUAAUUUCACACCUUUAUUGAAAAAUCUCAAAUUUAUGUUAAAAUGAGCUGUUUGUUUCCUUCCUUUCAUUAAAAUACAGCUGAGUCAUUUUCAUUUAAAACAACUCAUAUUCCCAUAAAUAAGAACAUUUGUCACAAAAAGUUAAUGAAUCUGGUAAAAUUUAGAACUAAGAUUCUAAAAGGUCUAUAGAUACGGCAAGAAAACUGUUUUUUGGAAAAUUGAAUUUUUAUUAAAAAAUCAACACAAUGUGAUUUCCCUUUAUUUCCUGAAGAAUAAUAAUUAGAUUAUGCUAUUCUUUUAUCAUCAUAGUUUUUUUUUAAAGGAAAAUCAUAAUAUGAUCAUCUAAAAGACUUAGGGAAAAAAAUACAUCUGUAUCACUUAUGGUGAGGUUGGCUUACCAGGAUUUAUGAAUAAAGAUUGUAGUGUCAAUGCAAAUUUUAAUUACAUUGCUUCUUUAAUGAAUCUUGAUAAGUCUAAGACAUUGAAGUUAUAGCAUUUUAUGGUUAUUAUUUUUAUUUUACCGAUCCACUUUUUCUUUAUCUAUGUACAUGAUACAGAUGUGACUGAAACACAUGGUAAACCGAAUGACCUUGAAGAAGAAAAGAACAAAUUUCCAUUUCAUGUAUUUUCAUUUAAAUUGACCACGUGACACACACAGUGGGACCAGGGAGAUUCACAUAAAAAAAAAUUUACAUUAAACUUCAGCAGAGACUUCCUAUCACUUUGGUCUUUGAUUCAUUACAGGUAACAUGAAUAUGAGAGGGAAUGGUACAUAUUUAGUAGUUAUCACAUGUCAUCACAACAUAGAUUAAAAAACAAAACCGUUUUUAUGAUUCACAAGUAUAGAUAUGAAUGUUACCUCCUUGAUACAGUUUAAAGUUGACUCUUUAAAGAUAGUCCUUUUAUACAAUUAAACCAUCCUAUCAACAUAUAUUUUAAGUAUAUAAAUUAUUAUAUAUGCACUUAUAAUUUUAUACUGGAAAUUAGGAGCUAGUAAACUAAUUUCAGUUUUGCCAGUUGUUUAAAUUUUUCUUUAACGUGAACCAAAACCUUUUUCGAUUCCAUUAUUAUGUUAGUAAUAGUAAUAUAUGAGUGUUACCAGAACAUUAAUGAUUGGAAUAUUUAGCAAAACCCAUUAAUGAUGGUGUGAGUUAAGGACUAUCCCUAUAUUUCAGGUAUAUGGCAGUUAUGGUGAGAACGUACAACCAGAAUAAUCACAAUUUAUUUGUUACAGUGAAUUCCAUUUUACGAAGAACUGGCAGGUUUUUUAAUCUGAACAAUAUUCAUACCAACUAACAUACUUAAGAGGUACUCAGAUGCUUGCUGAAUAAAUGUAGUUUAAGAUAAUACUUUUGAAAGUUGGCUGACAUAAGAAAAAUGGUAAUCUUUAAUGGGAAAUUGCAGCCUUUGGUGUUUAUUUACAAAGAGUUGGGAACUUUUUAAAUGCUGUUAACCCUUUAUAUUGGUUUGAAUCUCAUCUGGGAUAAUUGAGAAGGCUCAUUGUCAUUUUGAGGAUCCCAGACUCCCACAAAAAAAAAGAUGAGAGUGGGGUGUUGACUAGAGAGCUCCAAGUGAUAAAAUCUAGGAAAGAACACUAAAAAAAGGCGUCAGAAGGUUUGGGUUUAAGCCCGCUAAUAUGUGUUUAUUACUUACCUAUAAAAAGAUUACUUAUCUAUAAAAAGGUGAUCUCUACCUACUUUAAGAAUUACUACAUUCAUGAAAUUAGAGUAAGUAUGUGAAAGUACAUACGAGUUGAGUAUUCCUUAUCCAAAAUGCUUGGGACCAGAAAUGUUUUAGAUUUUGGAUUUUUUCAAAUUUUGAGAUAUUUGUGUUAUAUACUUAAAGUGGAGCAUAACAUUUCCUUUGAGUGCCAUGUUAAUGCUCAAAAAGUUUCUUUUUUUUUUUUUUUUGGAUUUUUGAAUUAGGGAUACUCAACCUGUUCUUGGAAAUCUGUAACAUAUGGUAUGCAUGUAAAUUGAUGGUUCAAAUAAUCACUAAUACUACUCACAUUGCUGCCACUGCUGAUGCCUUAUAACUAGUAUCAGAAGAGCCUCUUGGGAUGUUUAUACUGUAGUCUACCCUUAUCUUUAGGGAAUACAUUCCAGCAUUCCCAGUGGAUGUCUAAAACUGCAGAUAGUACUGAACCCUGUAUGCAUUGUUUUUUCCUAUACAUACAUACAUCCCUAUGAUAAAGUUUAAAUUAUAAAUUAGGCACAAUAAGAGAACAACAAGAUAGAACAAUUAUAACAGUAUAGCAUAAUGUCAGUUAAUGUGAAUGUGGCACUGUACUCACCCUUCUUGUGUUGAUGUGAAAUUAUGAGAUGAAGUAAGGUGAAUAAUGUAGGCAUUGUAAGCAUUGUGAUGUAGUAUUAGGCUACUACUGACCUUGAACACAAGCAUUGUGAUACCUUAACAGUUAAUCUGAUAACCCAGAUGGCUACUAGGUGACUUACAGGUAGAUAAGGUAUAUAGCAUGGAUACACUGGACAAAGGCAUGAUUCACAUCCUCAUGGGGACAGUGCAAGAUUUCAUCAUGCUACUCAGAAUGGCGUGCAGUUUAAAACUUAAGAAUUGUUUAUUUCUGGAAUUUUCAUAUAAUAUUUUUGGACUACAGCUGACUACGGGUAACUGAAACUGUGGAACAUGAACCCACCGAUAAUGGAAGGCUACUGUAUUUUAAUAUUUGCCAACACUGAGCAUUUGAAAUGAGCUACUUUGGCAGGAAAGAUUAUAAAUAAUUGAGUAGAUAUCAAUGGAUGAGCAUCAUAGUGCUCUAUCAGCCCUUUGGGAGACCAUGAGUAACCUAUCAUUUGGUUUUAGCUCUUUGUCUUGAUUCACUUUAUCAAAAUGGGACUAUAGAUGACUUGUGGUAGGUUCUAGAGUGCAAGAAAUGAGAAAAUAAGUGAAUGAGCUUUGCCCAGCCACAGAUUCUUAACAGUGCUGAGGGAAUUGUCCUGAGGUCUUUGCAAAAUCCUAAAUUAAUGAUUAUCACUAUAACAGAUUUUUCUUUACUUCUUUCCAUGUAACAUGUAUUUUCUUCCAACAGAUAUUUUUAAUUGACUUCUUCAGAUCAACAUUAGUAGGUGACGUUUUAAUAAGCAUUCUACAUUGUUUCCAGCAUUUACCUGAUGAAAUUAGGAUAAAAUGCCAUUUCUGACUGGUUACUAGCUUCCAAACAGCAGCCUUGUAGAACCUGCCAUUCAGAUUCAUGAGUCAGCAGAAUUUAUAAAUUAUGAUAGGUCAUGGAUCUUUGUUUUUUUCCCCAGAUUGUCAAAAACACAUGCCAAGUGUUGUGCAGCUUUAUGUACUCUUUCUUUAUAUACUAGCCAACAGCCUACAAUGGUAGUUCUCAUCGUGUGGUCUGUGUACCUCUGGGAGUCCCUGGUUCCUUUCAGUGUCCCUUUCUUCAAGGUCAAAUCUGUGUUGCUAGUAAUACUAAGAAGUUAUUUACCUUUUUCAAUGUGUUGACAUUUCCACUGAUGAUAAGGAGUAAGGAGUAAAAGUUCUGGCUCCUUAGAAUGAAUGAAGGCAAUUACAUGAAACCUUACUAAUAAUAUUCUAUAUGUUAUUUCUACAUGCCUGUAGUUUUUUUAAAAAGCUAGUUAGUUUCACUUAGGAAUGUUCUUGAAGCAAUAAAAAUAAUUUUAUUAAGCCUCAAUACUCUAGUACAUGUCUUUGAAUAUUCUGUAUGAUGAAACGGGAAGUACUGUACACACAAAAUAAAACUCGGUGAACCAGUAUUUUCCACAUGACCCAUUCAUUAUGUUACAAAAUUAUGCAUGAGUGAAAAUUUCAUUUACUGUCCAAGAGAGACCAAUUUUAGAUUUUACAUUGUAACUAACUUUUAGGAAACUAUCACCUGUUAAUUUUGGCCUAGUGUAAAAGAACAGUUUCCAUAGGUAUGGUAAAAAGCAAUUGAAUUACUGUUUUCUUUUUCAACUGCAUAACUGUGUAAUGCCAGAUAAUCUUCAUACCAUAGGGGAAAAAUACUUUUUUUCAACCCUCAUAGAUUCUUCAUUGGAUAUGGAUACCUAUAACAAAAGACAGAAGUUUAUUGACAUGUAUAUUUUAUAUAUACAUGGGAGACACCCAUGGAAUUAGUAGUUUUCAAGGUGGCUUUGAAUAGAGCAUUUUCAACAAAGAACAGUAAGUUUUUAGAGAAUACAAGACUGAGGAAAAGGACUUUGAAUCUGUAGCCGUAGUAAAUUUUGGAAGGGCAAAUCAAUAUGGCGGGUAGAGGCUAGUUGGUGAAGCUUAUUAACACAGAUUCUUUUCCAGGCUAAAGUUGUCUUCAGUGGUUAACCUUUGUUUCUCCUAGUAGAGAGGUGGGCAGGAUACCUUUUGUCUUUGCAAAUCUAUGUCUUGAUUUAGGCAAGUGGAAGGCAGAGAGGUUUCUUGCAUCUGCUCCUUCAAAACUACCUUCAGUAGAACAAUCCUUCCUAUUUUGGGGUAGCAUAUUCUGGUUUCCCAGAACAUACUUCAGUCAAAACAACAUAUCACAGCAGAUUAAAUACAGAGCCAGAUAUGACAACUCAACUAUUUUCUAGUAAGCCAGAUAUGGAAAGACAUUUGAAAAUACAAAACAAUGCCACUCUUCUCAUUUCGGAAAAUAGAUUUUUCAUAGAAGUUUCACUUUUAUUUAUUUUUUAUUUUUAAAUUAGUGGAGAACUAUUUAAUUUUUUUUUUUUUAGUUUUAAUGUCUAGUAUGGGAGAUACUAAUAGUAACAGACCAAAUAAACAAAGGCUCUUUGAGGCUCUCAAUUUUUAAGAAUAUAAAGGGAUCCUGAGACUUAAAAAUUUGAAAACUGCUAAGCUCUCUCUCACUGUGUGACUCGCCUGCUCGCCCUUUGCCUUCUGCCAUGAUUCUAAGUUUCCUGAGCCCUCACUAGAAGCUAAGCAGAUGCUGGUGCCAUGCUUCUUUUGUAUAUAGCCUGCUGAAGAGUGAACCAAAUAAACCCUCUUUUCUUUAUAAAUUUCACAGCCUCAGGUAUUUAUAGCAACACAGAGAUUAAAAUCUUAUUAGGGCAAGGGGUAUAGCUGGUCCUAAAAUUGUAAGAUUAGGAACUAUACUUUGUAUUCUAGUUCAUAAGUAUAAAAGCCCUGGAUGAGAAAUUGAUCUGAGGAAAGCUUUAUUGCAAAUUAAAGGACUCAGGAGAAUAGAUAUCGCUGGGCAAUGGAGGAUAUCUCAUCAUACCCCCCUUGAGCAGUUUGCUUUUAUCAUGACUUUGAGCACUAUCCUUUAUGUCUCUGUUCCUCAAUUUCUCCAGUUAUAAAAUAGGACCAUUUUUACAUCAGCGCCUCCUCUCCCUGUCUUACAGGGGUUUGACAAGGAUCAAAUGAGUUGCUUUAAAGAGAACAUGUGAGAUAAGAUAUCUCCUCACAGUAGGUUUCCAGGAUCCUGUCCAGGAUGAUCACAGUCAGCAUGGGGUUAAUACACAGAUUCAAGAGGCAUAUCAAAGGAGAUCUGAUAAGAUUUAGUGACUGGAUGAAUACAGGGAAUAAACAGAAAUUAGUUAAAAAUUAUUCUAAGGAGCCAGAUGCUGUGGCUCAUGCCUGUAAUCCUAGCUCUUUGGGAGGCUGAGGCGGGCAGAUUACUUCAGCCUAGGAGAUCGAGAGCAACCUGGGCAACAUGGUGGGACCCAGCUCUACAAAAAAUACAAAAAUUGGCGUGGCACAUGCCGGUAGUCCCAGCUAGCUCCUUGGGAGGCUGAGGUGGGAGGAUCGCUUGAGCCUGUGAGGUUGAGGCUGCAGUGAGCCGUGAUUGUUCGUGCCACUGCACUUUAGCCUGGGUGAGAGAGCGAGAUCCUGUCUCUUAAAAAAAAAAAAAAAAAAAAAAAAAAAAGUUUGUUCUGAGGGCUUAAUUGUCAAUAUUUUAGUAACAAAUUGGAGGAAUUGGAGAGAAAAGCAAAAAAUAGAUAUUUAAAAACCCAGGCUUUUAAGAUCAGGAUUGUAGGAUUGUAGCACAGAAGUUAAAGAAAAGUGGCCAGAAAAAUAAUUAAGGACAAAACAGGUAGGGCAUGGAUGGCUGUUUAAGGUUGGCUUUCAGGAAGCAGAGGAGUUUUGUAAGACAAUAGGCAAGCAUCGAAAAGAAACUUGGAUUAUUAUAACAUGUAGCAGAAAAAAUGAAAAACAAAACAAAAAAAACUUGGGUUAGCGUCUAAUGGUCGGGGCUGGUUAUACAAUUUGUGGGAUACAGUGUGAAUGAAAAUGAAAUGCAGGCCUUUGUUCAAAAAGCAAGGGGAAAAGUACAGUUAAGAGUGCUAAUGUUUAAAGCUUUUUUCCUUUGGGAAGAAAAACAUGGUAGAGUUAAUAGCAAUAAAUAAGUAAACACAAAUUCAAAAUUAUGUUUGUGGGUAUCAUGCUUUUAUAAAAGAUAGUAAAUAAAUAAUACCUUAUCACUGUGAAAUCUUGAUUAAUCAUGACUUUCUGGCUCUUUUUUCUGCAAAUUCAUUUUAGUCAUCAAAAUUUAUACUUUUAUAAAGUUUCAUUUUUAAUUUAUAUAAUUGGAAGUAAUGUCAAUUAUGUUUGGCAAAUGCAAGAUUACAAAUAUUUUUUGAUAAUUUUUGAUUUUGAGGACAGGCCUUGUACUGAUGCCACUGUUAAGAACAUUUUAUAGGCUGUGACAACAUUAGGAUAAAUUUCUGAUAAAUUAUUUCAAAAUCUAAAUUUAGAACAUCUAGAGCUAAUUUUUAGAACAAUUUUUCUAAAAGCUUUAACUCUACAAAUCAGUUCUGUGUAUAGAUUUAAUUCUAAGUGUAGAUUUAUACAGGGGUAUUUAAAUAUUCUUUCUGCUAUUUCUUGUAACUUGGAAGUUGUACAACUUCCAAGAAACCAAAUGACUUCAUGACUUGUAUAUAAUUCAGAAUGUCUGUUUGUGCAUCCUACCUCAUAUCUUCAGGUAUGAAGAUAUGGAAACAUUAAAUUUAAAAUAAUCCUUCUCAUUAACAGUUGGUUCUUCAUUAAAACAGUUGGUUCUCAUACAAAAAUAUUGUUCUUUUCAACCAAAUGUGACAAUCUUUAUAUUCAAUUUCUCUUUCUAAAGCUAUUGCUAUUUGGUUUGCAAUGUUGCAGUGGUUUAUAAAACUGGAGAUUAUAAAUGCCUUGAUGAAUUCUGAUAUAUUUUUGGUGCCAUGACUUGGAUACUUUGCAAUAAUAUGCUGACAAAGGUUUUACUCUCUGAGCACCAACACUUCCUGUCCUGGUCCUUAGGCUGGAGAGUUAAUAUUUGCGCAUAUACUGUUAGGAUAGGUUCCAGGAAGAGGAGUACUUUGGCUUUCCACUGUAUAUCCCCAGUGCUGAGCCGCUCUUUCAUGGGGCUGCUGCCAUCAUUGCCAUUGCCAAUCUGGGCUCAGUCCUGGCCACUGCCUUGAGUGCCCUGUGUUGUCCACGUCUGUCCCAGGUAUUCACAUUUGGGCCCAGGCAGCCAGUCCAGCUGCUUAGUGCAUAUGCUGACACUUGACAUAUUUCCUCUGUUCUGUGCUCCAUUGUCCCACUGGUCUUCAUCUACAAAGUACAAGUUCAAAGUCAUUAACAAGUUCAAGAUGGCGACAAAGGACCGUUCAACUAAAUAGAGGCCCCUUUUGAGAGCAAGCCCAUGUGUGACUGCACAAGUUACAUACCUGGAGAAGAUGGUAUAAACUGGUCCAUCAGUGACAAAGACAUUGAGGCCCAGAUAGCUAAUAACCGAACACCUGGAAGAUGGACCCAGCGGUACUAUUCAGCCAACAAAAACAUUAUCUGUAGAAAUUGUGACAAACGUGGUCAUUUAUCAAAAAACUGCCCCUUACCACGAAAAGUUCGUCGCUGCUUCCUGUGCUCCAGGAGAGGACAUCUCCUGUAUUCCUGUCCAGCCCCCCUUUGCGAAUACUGUCCUGUGCCUAAGAUGUUGGACCACUCAUGUCUUUUCAGACAUUCCUGGGAUAAACAGUGUGACCGAUGUCAUAUGCUAGGCCACUAUACAGAUGCUUGCACAGAAAUCUGGAGGCAGUAUCACCUAACGACCAAACCUGGACCACCCAAAAAGCCGAAGACCCCUUCAAGACCAUCAGCCUUAGCAUAUUGCUAUCACUGCGCGCAAAAAGGCCAUUAUGGACACGAAUGUCCAGAAAGAGAAGUGUAUGACCCGUCUCCAGUAUCUCCAUUCAUCUGCUACUAUGAUGACAAAUAUGAAAUUCAGGAGAGAGAAAAGAGACUAAAACAAAAAAUAAAAGUACUCAAGAAAAAUGGGGUUAUCCCAGAGCCAUCCAAGCUACCUUAUAUAAAAGCAGCAAAUGAGAACCCCCACCAUGAUAUAAGGAAGGGCCGUGCCUCAUGGAAAAGCAACAGGUGGCCUCAAGAAAAUAAAGAAACACAAAAAGAAAUGAAGAACAAGAAUAGAAACUGGGAGAAGCACAGGAAGGCUGACAGACAUCGUGAAGUGGAUGAGGAUUUUCCCAGGGGCCCCAAAACCUACUCUUCUCCUGGCAGUUUUAAAACCCAGAAGCCUUCUAAGCCCUUUCACCGUUCAUCACAUUACCACACGUCAAGAGAAGACAAGUCUCCCAAGGAAGGCAAGAGGGGCAAGCAGAAGAAAAAGGAGAGGUGCUGGGAAGAUGAUGACAAUGAUAACUUAUUUCUUAUUAAGCAGAGAAAAAAAAAGUCUUAAGCCGUCAGGCAGCCUCUGAUGUGGCUUUUCAUUGUUCAUUUGGCCUUUGUGUCUAUAACCUUCUGGCACUGUGUUUAUUAUCUAUGAUUAAAUAAAGUGAGUUUUUGGUUUUGUUUUUUUAAUUUCAGCCAUUCCUAGAGUUACUGAAUAUCCAUGGAGAUCUCAAUUCUCUGUGUCCAACAGGAUAUUAGGUAAGAAAGUACAAAGAUAAACCUGGACUUCUCCUAUUCCAAUAUGUCAUCUUUACUCAGAAUCCUAGGGAUAGGUAGAAGAAUUCAUCUUUUCAAGAAAGUGUUUUAAAAAUACUUUGGGAAAAAAACUGCAUCAAAGGUAAUUUAUCCUCAAAUUAAAUCCUUGCAGGAAGAGAAAUUAACACUAAGAAAAAGUCAUCAAUAUUUUUCAACUUUUUUUUUUUUUUUUUUUACUUUGGAAAGGACAAUAACUAUAAACCUAUAUCCAGAUUUUCUUUCUGCUGAAGCUGUUGUCAGAAUCUUCCUUUGGACAAAACAUCACUAGCUGACUAUAAAAACAAAAGUGUCAUCAUUGAAGCCCUGAAGAGGCAGGGAAUUGAGCUUCAGCAAAAUACAGGAAAAGAACUAUCCAGUAUAAAUGUCAGAAGACAGAUUUCCUAAACAAGUAAAAGAGACAUCAAAAAUUUUAACAUAAUCACAAUGAAAUCAUUUUUUACCACUUUUACAGCGGUGUUUCAAGCGGACUGUCACUCAGAUCUGCAGAGAUGAAUAUUACUCAAAAAAUUUUUUUGUUCUCUUGCAUUUUUUUCAACUACCGCAAAGCUAUACAGAUUUUUUUGUACUUGUGGAUCUUUUGUACUUCUCAUAACCUAAUGUCAGACUAAGAAAAAUAAAAUAUCUGAGAGUAAA